AGUGUCUCAGCCACAGCGGCUUCACCAUGCACAGCUGGGAGCGCCUGGCAGUUCUGGUCCUCCUAGGAGCGGCCGCCUGCGGUGAGGAGGCCUGGGCCUGGGCGGCGCCGCCCCGUGGUCGGAUCCUGGGCGGCAGAGAGGCCGAGGCGCACGCGCGGCCCUACAUGGCGUCGGUGCAGCUGAACGGCGCGCACCUGUGCGGCGGCGUCCUGGUGGCGGAGCAGUGGGUGCUGAGCGCGGCGCACUGCCUGGAGGACGCGGCCGACGGGAAGGUGCAGGUUCUCCUGGGCGCGCACUCCCUGUCGCAGCCGGAGCCCUCCAAGCGCCUGUACGACGUGCUCCGCGCAGUGCCCCACCCGGACAGCCAGCCCGACACCAUCGACCACGACCUCCUGCUGCUACAGCUGUCGGAGAAGGCCACACUGGGCCCUGCUGUGCGCCCCCUGCCCUGGCAGCGCGUGGACCGCGACGUGGCACCGGGAACUCUCUGCGACGUGGCCGGCUGGGGCAUAGUCAACCACGCGGGCCGCCGCCCGGACAGCCUGCAGCACGUGCUCUUGCCAGUGCUGGACCGCGCCACCUGCAACCGGCGCACGCACCACGACGGCGCCAUCACCGAGCGCUUGAUGUGCGCGGAGAGCAAUCGCCGGGACAGCUGCAAGGGUGACUCCGGGGGCCCGCUGGUGUGCGGGGGCGUGCUCGAGGGCGUGGUCACCUCGGGCUCGCGCGUUUGCGGCAACCGCAAGAAGCCCGGGAUCUACACCCGCGUGGCGAGCUAUGCGGCCUGGAUCGACAGCGUCCUGGCCUAGGGUGCCGGGGCCUGAAGGUCAGGGUCACCCAAGCAACAAAGUCCCGAGCAAUGAAGUCAUCCACUCCUGCAUCUGGUUGGUCUUUAUUGAGCACCUACUAUAUGCAGAAGGGGAGGCCGAGGUGGGAGGAUCAUUGGAUCUCAGGAGUUCGAGAUCAGCAUGGGCCACGUAGCGCGACUCCAUCUCUACAAAUAAAUAAAAAAUUAGCUGGGCAAUUGGCGGGCAUGGAGGUGGGUGCUUGUAGUUCCAGCUACUCAGGAGGCUGAGGUGGGAGGAUGACUUGAACGCAGGAGGCUGAGGCUGCAGUGAGUUGUGAUUGCACCACUGCCCUCCAGCCUGGGCAACAGAGUGAAACCUUGUCUCUCUCUACAAAAAAAAAAAAAAAAUUCUGCGUGGUGGCUCA